GGAGCUCUUCUGCGUGGUGUUUGGGGAAUAACGGUGGCUCUUCUAACCUGUGAGGCUUCUAGGAGAGGUGAGGCUGUUUCCUUCCUCCCCCGCCGCCCUCUGUCCUCCUGUCGGCCUGGCCUGGCCAGCUGCGCACUCUUCUGCCCCUUCAGGGGCCUGUGUUUGAAUGCUGGGGACCGGCUGGCUUUUCCCGGGCAUGCUCAUGAUCCCUGUUUCUGGGACAGAACCACACCUCUGAGUCUGUUUCAGGAGGAGACUCAGAGAGGAGCACUGGACGCCCUGCUUCCCCCACCAGCCCUCCUGAGCUUCCCCCACCAGCCCUCCUUUGCUUCCCGGAGUGUCCGAAAUAUUUCAGAGCUCGUUUUUAAAUGACAGAGUCUCAGGCCAUGGUGGGCGCGUUGGCAGACAUAUUCAAGGGUGAGGGAGGUAUGAGACCCGCCGUCCUGACGCUCAGGGAAAGCGCGGCCUCCUCAUGGUCUCUUGGCUGCGUCCUUCCUCCCGGGUGCUUUGCCUGCUUGGCUUUGACGUCUCUCAGGACGACCAGACUGUCCAGGUUCCCUGCUGAGCCCCGGGGUGGGGGUGGCGGGUUCCCUCCUGGGCCCUGGUGUGGGGGCGGCGGGCUGUGCGUGCUUCCUGCCCAGCCAGGGGCUGCUCAUCUGCGUCUGCCCUGCAAACGGUGAAUCACAUGCCAACCCCCUGUUCAGCUUCAGUAAUGUGACCUCUGAGUUCACAAAAACACGAUGUGCACUUUAAAAGCAGGAGCGACGUGGUCCUUUUGACGUCUGCCACACUGACCAGAGCUACGCAGCUCUCACCUGCUCUUCCGCUUCACGUGGUUUGGUAGUAAGAUUUUCAUUUUGGGCUGGAAUGAUAAAAUCUUCAUGUUUUUGUGUUGGAAACCAUGUCGUACAGAUAUGCUCUCUGAGCAUCUGUUUGCUUAAGUGUUUCGUGGAGGAUUCGCUGAAGACGUACGAAGAGUUGGGCACUGCCCCAAGGAACUUGUGCCUGCCCCACCCGACAGCGCGCUCACGCCAGGGCCACGGCCAGAGUGUGCCGCCGUCUCGGCCACUCCUUCAGUCCGGAACGUUCCUCUUCUCUCCCUGGCCUCGAGGCGUGGCUGCCGUGCCUGUGUUCAGCUUCAGGUCAUGCCGCAGGCAGGGGCCCGAGUGCUGGGCGGCUCCUCCCACCCUGUCCCCCCGGGGCAGCUGCGGACACUUGGGACACCCAGUCCUAAGACAGCACUGGCCACGGACUCAGGAAGCGAUGACUCCACGUGGUUUGGGGUAUCAUGUAGCAUGAAGUGUGGCUCGGUGUAGCGUGUAGCAUGGUUCAGUGUAGUGUGUAGCGUGGCUUGCUGUAGCGUGUAGCAUGGUUCUGCAUAGCGUGGCUUGGUAUAGCGUGUAGCGUGGCUCUGUGUAGCGUGGCUCAGUAUAGCGCAUAGCGUGGUUCUGUGUGGCGUGGCUCGCUGUAGCGCAUAGCGUGGUUCUGUGUGGCGUGGCUUGGUGUAGUGUUUAGUGUGCUUUGGUGCACUGUGAGGGGCUGUCUGGGCCCAUUCCUCACCGUGUGUUCCCUGCAUCGUAACGUCCAUGUCUGGGCAUAGCUCUUCUUUCCAUCUCGUUCAGCUCGGGGCUCUGUCCCCCUGUGGCUCCCAUCUUCCCCAGCGCCCUCCUUUUCCCUCCCCCUCACUCACAUCCCUGCGUCUCACCUUGCGCCAGCCCUUAGCCAGUGCUGCAGAAACGUCAGCCAUGCAUGGAGUGAACUGGCCAUUUCUUGAGGUGCUCCCUGGUGGUAUGCGAGCACCUAAUUCCCUUUAUUCCUUUUCUGGGAGGGUUACAUGGCCUCUCAUGAUGAGCACUUGCCGGGGUUGGGAGGGGUCACUGCAGGCUCAGCUGCACUAGCAGGAGACCCACAGAGAGGGACCUCAACACCAGGGCCCCUCUCACCCCCCAGGACAAGGUGUCCAGAGGGUUGUCCCAGGCAGGGAGCCUCCAGCUUUCCUCUCUGCCCUCUGUGGCAUGCCAGCUUCAACCCAGGUGUUCCUGCCCCAGCCGCACGGGGGUGGUGGGCACCCGUCCGCAAUGUCACUGCAUACCUGUGGAUGGCGGGCACCGGGGCAUCCCUGACAGGUUGGUUUUCUGGGGCUGUGGGGAGUCUUGGGUGCUUACUCUAGGUCCUCACUGUUUUUACUGUGUGAACCCUGCGGGCUGGCUCCGCCUCCCAGGAGCCGCUCCCGCAUGCUGCAGCCUGGUGACCUCUGGGCUGGUGAGCUCAGCCUCUGUCCACGAGGCCAGGUGUCUGGGGAGGGCACUGGAAGCAGCUGGAGGCAGCAGGGCCUGACCUGCCCCAUCCCCUCGAGGGCACGAGCAGGCCCCCAGGGCUUGUCAAGGGCCAGGGCCUUCCCAUCUCUGCCUCCUUGCCUGGUCGGGUGUGCUCGGGGCCAUGGCACAGCGGGAGGGAAACAUGGGUGGGUGGGGUCUUUGGAGAGCUUUCUGGACGUGGUGUCGGGCAGGGUCCUGGCUGAGGGGUGCGUGAGUGGCUGCAGACAGUUGGCCAUGGCUUGUUGGAGGAGGGCAUAGCUGCAACCCGGCAUCCAGAUCGCGCAGGAAAGUGGGAUGCUGUCUCCGGGUUUACUUUUCCAUUUAAUUAGAAAUACUAGAGAUGUUUCCAUGGCUCCUUUUAAUGGAACAUUGAAAUUCUUCAUUGUCUCCAGCCAGAAUACAGAUAUUCUCACAGGCUGUGGGUCCUGAUCUUUCCAGGGCUUAGUUUUAGGUUCCACCCUCUGCUGGCUUGAAUAUGCACAGAUGUGGAUGCAGCAUUUCCAAGGACUCUGUGGACAGCAGCCGGGUGGGGGAAGCGCUGUCAGGCCGAAGCCCUGGGAGAGAAGCAGAGCUCCAGGGAGAGGAGCCGGCCCCGCAGAGGAGCCGCCAGGCGGUUGUAUGCAAAGCUCCUGGUGCCAAGAGUUGAACAGCUCCCACAAUGCCUAGUGGAUGCAGGGACUCAUCUGCUCAUGGGAAGCACCUUUUAUGGCAUUUUGAUUGAUUGCUAGUGCCAGCUGGAGAAGAAAUUAUCAGGUGCACUAAAAGGUAUAAUUACUUGAUAGACUCCUGUGUUGGGUGUGAUUAAUGUUCCUUUGGUGGAAAGCAGAGGGUGAGUUGAUAAGAAAGUGACAGCAGCAGAGUGUCCACCUGCUGAUGAACCACCCUGUGGACAGAGCCGGCUAGGAAGGCACGCACACCCCUUCCCCCGCUCGCGCACUUGGGUCACAACCAGCGCCGCACCGUCAGCUUGGCGGAUUCACUCAGAAACCAGCACCUGUGGUUCUGUGGCCUGGAGGGUUUCAGAUGCCCUAACCACUGGGUUCCUCAGAGCCAUCUCAGGGGGAGCCCCGUGGCCCUCCCGAUGAGGGUGCCAAGCAGAAGGGAAGGAGAAGCCACAGCCUCUGUGCCCGCCGGAGCUGGACGUCAGCUGCAGGCCUCAAGGCCACCACACAAAAUCAGUUGUAUUUCUUUUUUUUUUUUCUUUUUGAGAUGGAGUCUCGCCUUGUCACCCAGGCUGGAGUGUAGUGGCACGAUCUCGGCUCACUGCAAGCUCUGCCUCCUGGGUUCACGCCAUUCUCCUGCCUCAGCCUCCCGAGUAGCUGGGACUACAGGAACCUGCCAUCACGCCUGGCUGAUUUUUUGUAUUUUUAGUAGAGACUAGGUUUCACCGUGUUAGCCGGGAUGGUCUCGACCUCCUGACCUUGUGAUCCACCUGCCUCAGCCUCCCAAAGUGCUGGGAUUACAGGCGUGAGCCACCACACCUGGCAAAUCAGUUAUAUUUCUAUAUGCUGGGAGAAAAUGUCAAAAUGAAAAUGUUAAGUAUAGCAUUUAUAAUAACAUUCAGAACCAUAAAAUAGGAAAUUUUAACAAAAGAAAUGCAGCCUGUAUGCCUCGAAAGAUAGCACACAUUGCUGAAAGUAAGGAACACUUCAGUAAAUGGAGAGGUAUACCAUGUUCAUGAAUCAGUCUUCAUAUUGUUAAACUGUCCAUCGUCACCAAUUUGAGCUAUAGAUUCCAUGACAUCCCAAGCAAUCCCAGAAGGAUUGUUUUUUCCAGAAACAGAUAAACUGACUCUUAGAUGUAUAUGGAAAUGCCAAGGACCUACAUAGCCAAAACAAUUUUGAAGAAGAAUAAAGAUGCAGGAGGAGUCACACUACUUGAUUCCAGGAUUUACUGAAAAAUGAUCGUAAUGAAGACAGUGUGACACAGGUGUGUGGAGGGUUCCCUCGAGGGACAGAACUAACAGGAGAAAUAUAUAUAUAAAGGGGUUUAUUGAGUAUUAACUCCACGAUCACAAGUCCCCACGAUAGGUUGCCCGCAAGCUGAGGAGCAAGGAGAGCCGGUCCCGAGUCUCAGAACGGAAGAACCUGGAGUCCCAUGUUUGAGGGCAGGAGGCGUCCAGCACAGAAGAAAGAUGCGGGCUGGGAGGGUAGGCCCGUCUCCCCUCUUCUCCUUUUUCUGCCUGCUUUAUAUUCUCUGGCGGCUGAUGAGAUGGUGCCCACCAGAUUAAGCUUGGGUCCGCCUUCCCCAGCCCCCUGACCCAAACAGGAAUCUCCUCUGGCAACACCCUCACAGACACACCCAGGAUCAGUACUUUGCAUCCUUCAACCCAAUCAAGCUGACACUCAGUAUUAACCAUCACAAGGCGUGAGGACAGAUAGCUGCAUCCGCAAAAUAGAGAACCAAGAAAUAGUCCCACACCAAAGUCAGGAUCAAAUGAUUCCUGGACAAGCCACCAAGUCAAUUCAACUGAGAGAAAGAAGCCUUUGCACCAGUUGGUGCUGGAAGUUCUGGAUAUGCACCUGGAUAAGUGAACCCCCCUCCGUCACCACACACAAACGUUAAUUUGAGAUGGAUUGCAAACAUAAAAGCUAAAACCAUUAACACUUCUUGAAGGUAACAUAGAAUAUUUUGUAAUGUUAUGAUAGGCAAAAGUCUCUUAGGACACACAAAAAAAUUAACCAUAAAAGAAGAAAAUGGCUGGGUGCAGUGGCUCACACCUUUAACACCAGCAUGUUAGGAGGCUGAGGCAGGAGCGUCCCUUGAGCUCAGGAGUUCAAGCCCAGACUGGGCAACAUAGUGAGACCCUGAAAGAAAAAGAAACAAACACAUACAUUGGACUUCCUCAAAAUUAAAGUCUUCUGUUCUUCAAAAGACACCACCGAGAAAAUGACAAGGCACAGAUCAGGAGAAAAUAUUCACAAUGCCAUUAUGCCUGACAAGGAACCUGUAUCUGGAAUACAUAAAGAAUUCAUAAAGUUCAAUAAUAAAGAUAAUUUGAUUUUUUAAAGAGGGAAAGGAUUUUAGCAGGCACUUCACAAAAGGAAACAUGCAAAUGGCUCUCACGGCACUUGAAAAAUCCCUCAGAUGCACUGGCUAUUAGGGAAAUGCUGAGCGUAUCUACAUUGAGACAAUUCCUCCCCCCAAGAACAGCUGAAAUUAAACUGAGAUACUUCCUCCUCACAAGAACGGCAGUGCAGAAGUCACCACCACACAGCAGAGACGGGCGUCCUGUGGGCAGUGCAGAGUUCACCACCACGCAGCAGAGACGGGCGUCCUGUGGGCAGUGCAGAGGUCACCACCACGCAGCAGAGACAGGCGUCCCCACGGGCAGUGCAGAGGUCACCACCAUGCAGCAGAGACAGGCAUCCUGUGGGCGGUGCAGAGGUCACCACCACGCAGCAGAGACAGGUGUCCUGUGGGCGGUGCAGAGGUCACCACCACGCAGCAGAGACAGGCGUCCUGUGGGCAGUGCAGAGGUCACCACCACGCAGCAGAGACAGGCGUCCUCACAGGCAGUGCAGAGGUCACCACCACGCAGCAGAGACAGGCGUCCCCACGGGCAGUGCAGAGGUCACCACCACACAGCAGAGACAGGCGUCCUGUGGGCGGUGCAGAGGUCACCACCACGCAGCAGAGACAGGCGUCCUGUGGGCGAUGCAGAGGUCACCCCACGCAGCAGAGACAGGCGUCCUGUGGGCGAUGCAGAGGUCACCACCACGCAGCAGAGACGGCCGUCCCCACAGGCAGUGCAGAGGUCACCACCACGCAGCAGAGACAGGCGUCCCCACGGGCAGUGCAGAGGUCACCACCACACAGCAGAGACAGGCGUCCUGUGGGCGGUGCAGAGGUCACCACCACGCAGCAGAGACAGGCGUCCUGUGGGCGAUGCAGAGGUCACCCCACGCAGCAGAGACAGGCGUCCUGUGGGCGAUGCAGAGGUCACCACCACACAGCAGAGACGGGCGUCCCCACAGGCAGUGCAGAGGUCACCACCACGCAGCAGAGACAGGCGUCCCCACGGGCAGUGCAAAGGUCACCACCACACAGCAGAGAUAGGCGUCCUGUGGGCGAUGCAGAGGUCACCACCACGCAGCAGAGACAGGCGUCCUGUGGGCGGUGCAGAGGUCACCACCACGCAGCAGAGACGGGCGUCCCCACAGGCAGUGCAGAGGUCACCACCACGCAGCAGAGACAGGCGUCCUGUGGGCGAUGCAGAGGUCACCCCACGCAGCAGAGACAGGCGUCCUGUGGGCGAUGCAGAGGUCACCACCACGCAGCAGAGACAGGCGUCCCCACAGGCAGUGCAGAGGUCACCACCACACAUCAGAGACAGGCGUCCUGUGGGCGAUGCAGAGGUCACCACGACGCAGCAGAGACAGGCGUCCUGUGGGCGAUGCAGAGGUCACCACCACGCAGCAGAGACAGGCGUCCUGUGGGCGAUGCAGAGGUCACCACCACGCAGCAGAGACAGGCGUCCCCACAGGCAGUGCAGAGGUCACCACCACACAGCAGAGACAGGCGUCCCCACAGGCAGUGCAGAGGUCACCACCACGCAGCAGAGACAGGCGUCCCCACGGGCAGUGCAAAGGUCACCACCACACAGCAGAGACAGGCGUCCUGUGGGCAGUGCAGAGGUCACCACCACACAGCAGAGACAGGCGUCCUGUGGGCAGUGCAGAGGUCACCACCACGCAGCAGAGACAGGCGUCCUGUGGGCGAUGCAGAGGUCACCCCACGCAGCAGAGACAGGCGUCCUGUGGGCGAUGCAGAGGUCACCACCACACAGCAGAGACGGGCGUCCCCACAGGCAGUGCAGAGGUCACCACCACGCAGCAGAGACAGGCGUCCCCACGGGCAGUGCAAAGGUCACCACCACACAGCAGAGAUAGGCGUCCUGUGGGCGAUGCAGAGGUCACCACCACGCAGCAGAGACAGGCGUCCUGUGGGCGAUGCAGAGGUCACCACCACGCAGCAGAGACAGGCGUCCUGUGGGCGAUGCAGAGGUCACCACCACGCAGCAGAGACGGGCGUCCCCACAGGCAGUGCAGAGGUCACCACCACACAGCAGAGACAGGCGUCCCCACGGGCAGUGCAGAGGUCACCACCACGCAGCAGAGACAGGCGUCCCCACGGGCAGUGCAGAGGUCACCACCACACAGCAGAGACAGGCGUCCUGUGGGCAGUGCAGAGGUCACCACCACGCAGCAGAGACAGGCGUCCUGUGGGCAGUGCAGAGGUCACCACCACGCAGCAGAGACGGGCGUCCCCACAGGCAGUGCAGAGGUCACCACCACACAGCAGAGACAGGAGUCCUGUGGGCAGUGCAGAGGUCACCACCACGCAGCAGAGACAGGCGUCCUGUGGGCAGUGCAGAGGUCACCACCACGCAGCAGAGACAGGCGUCCUGUGGGCAGUGCAGAGGUCACCACCACGCAGCAGAGACGGGCGUCCCCACAGGCAGUGCAGAGGUCACCACCACACAGCAGAGACAGGAGUCCUGUGGGCAGUGCAGAGGUCACCACCACGCAGCAGAGACGGGCGUCCCCACAGGCAGUGCAGAGGUCACCACCACACAGCAGAGACAGGCGUCCCCACAGGCAGUGCAGAGGUCACCACCACGCAGCAGAGACAGGCGUCCCCACGGGCAGUGCAGAGGUCACCACCACACAGCAGAGACAGGCAUCCUGUGGGCAGUGCAGAGGUCACCACCACGCAGCAGAGACAGGCGUCCUGUGGGCAGUGCAGAGGUCACCACCACGCAGCAGAGACGGGCGUCCCCACAGGCAGUGCAGAGGUCACCACCACACAGCAGAGACAGGAGUCCUGUGGGCAGUGCAGAGGUCACCACCACGCAGCAGAGACAGGCGUCCUGUGGGCAGUGCAGAGGUCACCACCACGCAGCAGAGACGGGCGUCCCCACAGGCAGUGCAGAGGUCACCCCACACAGCAGAGACAGGCGUCCUGUGGGCGAUGCAGAGGUCACCACCACGCAGCAGAGACGGGCGUCCCCACAGGCAGUGCAGAGGUCACCACACUGAGCCAGACUGUCCUCGGCCUUCCCUGGGUUGAGCACCGGAUGAAAACCAUGUGCUUUGAGCCCUGGAAAGACAAUCAGCCCAGCCAGAGCCAGAGCCUGAAACAGGCAGCCCCCAGGGCGCAGCUGCAGGAAGCCGCAUCCUCUCGUGGGCUCCAGCAAGGCGGGGGACGCUGUGUUCCCUCAGUGGCUUCUUGGUGCCCCUUGAUGUCCAGGAGUGUGAGGUGAGGUGAGGGCUCUGAGCUGGGAAGCUGACAAGUCAGGGAGAAUGCCAGGCCAGACGCAUCGGCCUGCGGGGGCUGGAGCAGAGCCUGGCACUCACUGUACUUGCUCCGUCUCACUCCGGCUGCUGCGCUGGCCCAGGGCUGUCCACCCCAGGCGUGUGGCAGAGCAAGCCUGGCUCCCAGAGCUCCCCUCAGGCCCUGGAGCGGCAGGCAGUGGGCAUCCUCAGCCCAACCCAUGUCCGUGCCAUGCACAGGAUAGCUGAGCUUGCCGCUGCCACAGGGUGUCAGCGGGUUGGGGCAACAGACAGGGCCCCAGUGCUGGUGGCCAGGCUGGCUGUAUGUGUGGGUUGGCUGCCACCUGACUGCACUGAAACAAGAACCACCCCCACCCCACCCCCCACUGCUCUCCACCCGGUUCGGGGCCGGCCCUGGCUGGGCUUCGUGGAUCCUCAGGUUGUGCGGGUCAUGGCUUCCUGGGGCUGGGCCAGAGCCAUCAUGGAGUCAGCACGGUUCCUUGCAGACACAGGCGGGGCAGGCGGCGCCUCUCCACCUUCCUUGCCUCAAGCUGCGGGGACAGCACCAAAAAGCCACGUGGACCCAGAUGGCCUCGCCGGACUUCCUGACUCAGGGCUGUCUCCAGCCUACAUCCCACCGGGGCUGCACGCACAGACGGCUUCUCCUGGAGCCCUGGAGCAUUUCCCCCGUGUUUCGGCCAGGUUUUCUGCUUUAAAUGAGUUUAUUUCAGUCGUGUCAAAGUGAAGGUCUCUUUCACUCAGGACGUGAUCAAUGGCGUGGCCAUCAAGUCACAGCGUUGAAGGCAACAGAUGGCCUUUAAUGACGCUAUUUUAAAAAAUAAUUUCCCCUUUCUUUCCCCAUCCUGGUUUUGUGAGGACAGAGCAUCGGCAUCUCAGGGCGGGGGUGGGUCUGCCUACUCUGUGGCCAGCACGCAGCAGAUCCCUGUAGGUGGAGCCCCACAGCUCUGUGUCCCGGCACCUCUGUGCCACCUGCACAGGGGCAGAGGGUGGGUUUUCCGUGACGCCCCCUGGAGCCAAACCACCGUUGAUCACUUCCUCCUGAUGAACUGGGCUGUGUUGGGGUGCAGAGGUCUCGGUUGCGUAUGUUCUGGGAAUUGAGCCAGGGUCCUUGUUGCUGGGAAUUCUCAGACCUGGACAAUAUCAGUAGAGGAGACCACUUGAUUUUUAGUUUGACCCCUGGAGAAUUGAAAAGCUGGAAAUCUGUUUUCUGUACCUUCCCCCUCCCAACCCUCCCCCGACUCCCUACCUGGCUUCUGUCUGGAGAGGACGUCUGCAUGGCUGUCCUGGGGUGGCUGCAGGUGUGCAGAUGCUCACCGCCACUGUCUCCCCAUUCCUGCUGGAGCCCACUUUGGUGUGAGUGUUUGCCUGGCAGAGGCAUCGCAGGCCCACGGGAGGAUAAAGAGAAGCCAGAGAACUCAUAAUUCCAAAAGCUGGCAAAGUUAAAACGUGAUGUCUGGCCGGGUGCAGUGGCUCACACCUGUAAUCCCAGCACUUUGGGAGGCUGAGAUGGGCAGAUCACCUGAGGUCAGGAGUUCGAGACCAGCCUGGCCAACAUGGUGAAAUCCCGUCUGUACUAAAACACACACACACACACACACACACACACACACACACACACACACACACACAUAAAAAUUAGCAGGUAUGCUGGCGGGCGCCUGUAAUUCCAGUUAUUCAGGAGGCUGAGGCAGGAGAAUUGCUUGAACCUGGGAGGCGGAGGUUGCAGUGAGCCAAGAUCGUGCCAUUGCACUCCAGCCUGGGCAACAGAGUGAGACUCCAGCUCAAAAAAAUAAAAGAAAAGAAAAAAGAAAAGAAAAUAAUAAAAUAAAUAAAAUAAGAUGUCCAAACUCACACCUGUGCAGCUUACGGCUCUGCGAGGCUCACACCUGUGUGGCUCAUGGCUCUGGAGGGCUCACACCUGGCUACAGCACCCAGAGGUAGGGCCUUCUGAUGCUCCUUGUGUGCAAACUGUCUUGGUCCUCAUUAACACAAGAAGAAAAAGCAACGGCUGAAAUGUGGAAUACGUAAGCCCACAGUGUGAACCAUUUUGGGGUCAGAAUCGAGCAAAGGCCAGGAAGCCAUAGCCAGGCUGUGUGAUUGCAGGCACCGUGGAAACUCCAGUAACUAAGAUGGCACCAUGAAGAGCUGCCUGGGAUGUUACAGAAGCCUUAGGCCAGUCAGUGUGACAACUUAGAUGAGAUGGACAAAACCCUUGAAGAAGGGUGCGGGGGAGUGCCGGGUGCAGUGACUUCUUUACUCAAGGAAAGCCAGGAUUUGGGACGCGUGUCGGAGCUGAGCCCCACAUCUCUCUUUACACCCAGACCUGCUCACCUUUUGUGGGAUUCAGGCCCGAGUGUGCGGCAUCGUGCAGUGGAGCCUCCGACCCUCACGGGCACGGCACAUCCGGCGUCCAGGGCGUGUGCCUCCCACGUGUGUGCUGCCACCCCAAGCCUCGUGGGGUCGGAAGGAAGGUGCCAGGGGCUCAACAGGUUUGCGCCUUCGUCAUCUGCUCUUUUCCCACAGGCCCAGGACUGUCUGCAAAGCGCUUUACGCCGAGCAUGCUUCACCCCCGAGCCUGCCAGAGGGUCCGCAGCCCAUGGGAGGUGUGGGUCAUGGGCGGCGCUGAAAGGCAGACGUGGAGCGGUGCUGCCGACAUCAAGACCUGACUUUGAAGUCCACAGGCUGCUGCUUGGCAUCAGAGCCACUGAUGAAAUCACAUUAAACGUAAUGGAAUUGGUAUCGGCAUGCAGCCCUGUGAGGCCAGGAUCAGGCAGAUGUGCUGCCGUUUCCCUGACAGGCCCGCCCUGGUCCUGGGCAGCCACACUCCAGAACGAGAGUAAUUAUCCUAAUUGCUUUAUUGCAUCAGUGUGGGGGCAGCUCGGGUAGCUCAGAGGAAAAGGGGCUUCUUUCAGGGCCCAUCGGCUUCAGGGCGACAUGCUCCACCCGGAAGGGGCAGACCUCUGACUCCGGCACGGAGGCGUCGUGGGAAUUUUUAGAAAAUGAUAUCUAUGGCAUCCUGAUCUCUGGCCCCCAGCUGCAGCCCCCUGUGAGGCCGAGGCCCAGACCGGAGUCCCUGAAAGCGCUUUGUGCCUCCGACCUCCGGCGUUUUUGGCAGAGCUGGGGCAGGAGCCGGGGUGCUCCUCGCGGCUGAAGCGCAUCAGCCUCCAGGGCGAGGGUGUCUCAGAUCCCCGCACAGCCCGUCACACAGCCCCUGGGACAAUCACACAGGACAGUGCUCUCCUGUGAUCUUCAAAGGAUCUCCUGGGUUGUGGGGGUGCAAAAUAAAACUCUGCUACAAA